AGUCACUUGCCAUUUCUCAUAACAGCGUCAGAGAGAAAGAACUGACUGAAACGUUUGAGAUGAAGAAAGUUCUCCUCCUGAUCACAGCCAUCUUGGCAGUGGCUGUUGGUUUCCCAGUCUCUCAAGACCAGGAACGAGAAAAAAGAAGUAUCAGUGACAGCGAUGAAUUAGCUUCAGGGUUUUUUGUGUUCCCUUACCCAUAUCCAUUUCGCCCACUUCCACCAAUUCCAUUUCCAAGAUUUCCAUGGUUUAGACGUAAUUUUCCUAUUCCAAUACCUGAAUCUGCCCCUACAACUCCCCUUCCUAGCGAAAAGUAAACAAGAAGGAAAAGUCACGAUAAACCUGGUCACCUGAAAUUGAAAUUGAGCCACUUCCUUGAAGAAUCAAAAUUCCUGUUAAUAAAAGAAAAACAAAUGUAAUUGAAAUAGCACACAGCAUUCUCUAGUCAAUAUCUUUAGUGAUCUUCUUUAAUAAACUUGAAAGCAAAGAUUUUGGUUUCUUAAUUUCCACAAA